AGUUUUGCUGCUAGUCGCGGACGCAAUGGCUUCAAGGUUACUUCGCGGAGCUGGAACGCUGGCCGCGCAGGCCCUGAGGGCUCGCGGCCCCAGUGGCGCGGCCGCGAUGCGCUCCAUGGCAUCUGGAGGUGGUGUUCCCACUGAUGAAGAGCAGGCGACUGGGUUGGAGAGGGAGAUCAUGCUGGCUGCAAAGAAGGGACUGGACCCAUACAAUGUACUGGCCCCAAAGGGAGCUUCAGGCACCAGGGAAGACCCUAAUUUAGUCCCCUCCAUCUCCAACAAGAGAAUAGUAGGCUGCAUCUGUGAAGAGGACAAUACCAGCGUCGUCUGGUUUUGGCUGCACAAAGGCGAGGCCCAGCGAUGCCCCCGCUGUGGAGCCCAUUACAAGCUGGUGCCCCAGCAGCUGGCACACUGAGCACCUGCACUAAAUUACUCAAAAUGUGCUGUAAAGUUUCUUCUUUCCAGUAAAGACUAGCCAUUGCAUUGGCUCCUUCUCCCAUAGAUGGCUGGUCUUAUUUCUUACCCGUAUUCUUUGGUAGGCAUGGAAUAUGCUUAUUUUGGGAAAAGCUGUCUGUUAAUGCUAGCUUGCCAUCCACUUACUGAAAGUGUAUAACCAGUGUAUAGUGCUUAGAUUAAUAAUAAGAAUAGAUCGACAACCCGUAAUGCAAUGAAUGGGACCACCUGGUAUGA